GGACUCCGGCGGGACCUGCUCGGAGGAAUGGCGCCGCCGGGUUCAAGCACUGUCUUCCUGUUGGCCCUGACAAUCAUAGCCAGCACCUGGGCUCUGACGCCCACUCACUACCUCACCAAGCAUGACGUGGAGAGACUAAAAGCCUCGCUGGAUCGCCCUUUCACAAAUUUGGAAUCUGCCUUCUACUCCAUCGUGGGACUCAGCAGCCUUGGUGCUCAGGUGCCAGAUGCAAAGAAAGCAUGUACCUACAUCAGAUCUAACCUUGAUCCCAGCAAUGUGGAUUCCCUCUUCUACGCUGCCCAGGCCAGCCAGGCCCUCUCAGGAUGUGAGAUCUCUAUUUCAAAUGAGACCAAAGAUCUGCUUCUGGCAGCUGUCAGUGAGGACUCAUCUGUUACCCAGAUCUACCAUGCAGUUGCAGCUCUAAGUGGCUUUGGCCUUCCCUUGGCAUCCCAAGAAGCACUCAGUGCCCUUACUGCUCGUCUCAGCAAGGAGGAGACUGUGCUGGCGAGGGUGUGGAGCACCGUUCUGGAAUCCCGUUCGUUGUUUAGCAAGAGAACAGUCCAGGCUCUGCAGACAGCAUCCCACCUGUCCCAGCAGGCUGACCUGAGGAGCAUCGUGGAGGAGAUUGAGGACCUUGUUGCUCGCCUGGAUGAACUCGGGGGCGUGUAUCUCCAGUUUGAAGAAGGACUGGAAACAACAGCGUUAUUUGUGGCUGCCACCUACAAGCUCAUGGAUCAUGUGGGGACUGAGCCAUCCAUUAAGGAGGAUCAGGUCAUCCAGCUGAUGAACGCGAUCUUCAGCAAGAAGAACUUUGAGUCCCUCUCCGAAGCCUUCAGCGUGGCCUCUGCAGCUGCUGUGCUCUCGCAUAAUCGCUACCACGUGCCAGUUGUGGUUGUGCCUGAGGGCUCUGCUUCCGACACUCAUGAACAGGCUAUCUUGCGGUUGCAAGUCACCAAUGUUCUGUCUCAGCCUCUGACUCAGGCCACUGUUAAACUAGAACAUGCUAAAUCUGUUGCUUCCAGAGCCACUGUCCUCCAGAAGACAUCCUUCACCCCUGUAGGGGAUGUUUUUGAACUAAAUUUCAUGAACGUCAAAUUUUCCAGUGGUUAUUAUGACUUCCUUGUCGAAGUUGAAGGUGACAACCGGUAUAUUGCAAAUACCGUAGAGCUCAGAGUCAAGAUCUCCACUGAAGUUGGCAUCACAAAUGUUGAUCUUUCCACCGUGGAUAAGGAUCAGAGCAUUGCACCCAAAACUACCCGGGUGACAUACCCAGCCAAAGCCAAGGGCACAUUCAUCGCAGACAGCCACCAGAACUUCGCCUUGUUCUUCCAGCUGGUAGAUGUGAACACUGGUGCUGAACUCACUCCUCACCAGACAUUUGUCCGACUCCAUAACCAGAAGACUGGCCAGGAAGUGGUGUUUGUUGCCGAGCCAGACAACAAGAACGUGUACAAGUUUGAACUGGAUACCUCUGAAAGAAAGAUUGAAUUUGACUCUGCCUCUGGCACCUACACUCUCUACUUAAUCAUUGGAGAUGCCACUUUGAAGAACCCAAUCCUCUGGAAUGUGGCUGAUGUGGUCAUCAAGUUCCCUGAGGAAGAAGCUCCCUCGACUGUCUUGUCCCAGAACCUUUUCACUCCAAAACAGGAAAUUCAGCACCUGUUCCGCGAGCCUGAGAAGAGGCCCCCCACCGUGGUGUCCAAUACAUUCACUGCCCUGAUCCUCUCGCCGUUGCUUCUGCUCUUCGCUCUGUGGAUCCGGAUUGGUGCCAAUGUCUCCAACUUCACUUUUGCUCCUAGCACGAUUAUAUUUCACCUGGGACAUGCUGCUAUGCUGGGACUCAUGUAUGUCUACUGGACUCAGCUCAACAUGUUCCAGACCUUGAAGUACCUGGCCAUCCUGGGCAGUGUGACGUUUCUGGCUGGCAAUCGGAUGCUGGCCCAGCAGGCAGUCAAGAGGAUCGCUGCAGAGCAGAGCAGUAGAUUGGCAAAAUAUAGGACACUACGAACAGCACAUUAGUUCCAGAAGAAAGAUGGAAAUUCUGAAAACUGAAUGUCAAGAAAAGGAGUCAAGAACAAUUCACAGUAUGAGAAGAAAAAUGGAAAAAAAAAACUUUAUUUAAAAAAGAAAAAAGUCCAGAUUGUAGUUAUACUUUUGCUUGUUUUUCAGUUUCCCCAACACACAGCAGAUACCUGGUGAGCUCAGAUAGUCUCUUUCUCUGACACUGUGUAAGAAGCUGUGAAUAUUCCUAACUUACCCAGAUGUUGCUUUUGAAAAGUUGAAAUGUGUAAUUGUUUUGGAAUAAAGAGGGUAACAAUAGGAA